GCUCUCUCGCGCUACCCUCCCGCCGCCCGCGGUCCUCCGUCGGUUCUCUCGUUAGUCCACGGUCUGGUCUUCAGCUACCCGCCUUCGUCUCCGAGUUUGCGACUCGCGGACCGGCGUCCCCGGCGCGAAGAGGCUGGACUCGGAUUCGUUGCCUGAGCAAUGGCUGCCAUCCGGAAGAAACUGGUGAUUGUUGGUGAUGGAGCCUGUGGAAAGACAUGCUUGCUCAUAGUCUUCAGCAAGGACCAGUUCCCAGAGGUGUAUGUGCCCACAGUGUUUGAGAACUAUGUGGCAGAUAUCGAGGUGGAUGGAAAGCAGGUAGAGUUGGCUUUGUGGGACACAGCUGGGCAGGAAGAUUAUGAUCGCCUGAGGCCCCUCUCCUACCCAGAUACCGAUGUUAUACUGAUGUGUUUUUCCAUCGACAGCCCUGAUAGUUUAGAAAACAUCCCAGAAAAGUGGACCCCAGAAGUCAAGCAUUUCUGUCCCAACGUGCCCAUCAUCCUGGUUGGGAAUAAGAAGGAUCUUCGGAAUGAUGAGCACACAAGGCGGGAGCUAGCCAAGAUGAAGCAGGAGCCUCACUGUGUCGCCAGGCUGGAGUGCUGUGGCACGAUCUUGGCUCAACUGCAACCUCCGCCUCCCAGAUUUAAGCGAUUCCCCUGCCUCAGCCUCCUGAGUAGCUGGGGUUACAGGCGCCCACUACCACACCCAGGAGCCGGUGAAACCUGAAGAAGGCAGAGAUAUGGCAAACAGGAUUGGCGCUUUUGGGUACAUGGAGUGUUCAGCAAAGACCAAAGAUGGAGUGAGAGAGGUUUUUGAAAUGGCUACGAGAGCUGCUCUGCAAGCUAGACGUGGGAAGAAAAAAUCUGGGUGCCUUGUCUUGUGAAACCUUGCUGCAAGCACAGCCCUUAUGCGGUUAAUUUUGAAGUGCUGUUUAUUAAUCUUAGUGUAUGAUUACUGGCCUUUUUCAUUUAUCUAUAAUUUACCUAAGAUUACAAAUCAGAAGUCAUCUUGCUACCAGUAUUUAGAAGCCAACUAUGAUUAUUAACGAUGUCCAACCCGUCUGGCCCACCAGGGUCCUUUUGACACUGCUCUAACAGCCCUCCUCUGCACUCCCACCUGACACACCAGGCGCUAAUUCAAGGAAUUUCUUAACUUCUUGCUUCUUUCUAGAAAGAGAAACAGUUGGUAACUUUUGUGAAUUAGGCUGUAACUACUUUAUAACUAACAUGUCCUGCCUAUUAUCUGUCAGCUGCAAGGUACUCUGGUGAGUCACCACUUCAGGGCUUUACUCCGUAACAGAUUUUGUUGGCAUAGCUCUGGGGUGGGCAGUUUUUUGAAAAUGGGCUCAACCAGAAAAGCCCAAGUUCAUGCAGCUGUGGCAGAGUUACAGUUCUGUGGUUUCAUGUUAGUUACCUUAUAGUUACUGUGUAAUUAGUGCCACUUAAUGUAUGUUACCAAAAAUAAAUAUAUCUACCCCAGACUAGAUGUAGUAUUUUUUGUAUAAUUGGAUUUCCUAAUACUGUCAUCCUCAAAGAAAGUGUAUUGGUUUUUUAAAAAAGAAAGUGUAUUUGGAAAUAAAGUCAGAUGGAAAAUUCAUUUUUUAAAUUCCCGUUUUGUCACUUUUUCUGAUAAAAGAUGGCCAUAUUACCCCUUUUCGGCCCCAUGUAUCUCAGUACCCCAUGGAGCUGGGCUAAGUAAAUAGGAAUUGGUUUCACGCCUGAGGCAAUUAGACACUUUGGAAGAUGGCAUAACCUGUCUCACCUGGACUUAAGCAUCUGGCUCUAAUUCACAGUGCUCUUUUCUCCUCACUGUAUCCAGGUUCCCUCCCAGAGGAGCCACCAGUUCUCAUGGGUGGCACUCAGUCUCUCUUCUCUCCAGCUGACUAAACUUUUUUUCUGUACCAGUUAAUUUUUCCAACUACUAAUAGAAUAAAGGCAGUUUUCUAAA